ACGACGCGCCGGAAAGCAACGGCAAGGGCCGCAGCCAGCACCGGGCGGAGAGGGCUACCAUGGGGAAAAUCGCGCUGCAACUCAAAGCCACGCUGGAGAACAUCACCAACCUCCGGCCCGUGGGCGAGGACUUCCGGUGGUACCUGAAGAUGAAAUGUGGCAACUGUGGUGAGAUUUCGGACAAGUGGCAGUACAUCCGGCUGAUGGACAGUGUGGCACUGAAGGGGGGCCGUGGCAGUGCUUCCAUGGUCCAGAAGUGCAAGCUGUGUGCAAGAGAAAAUUCCAUCGAGAUUUUAAGCAGCACCAUCAAGCCUUACAAUGCUGAAGACAAUGAGAACUUCAAGACAAUAGUGGAGUUUGAGUGCCGGGGCCUUGAACCAGUUGAUUUCCAGCCGCAGGCUGGGUUUGCUGCUGAAGGUGUGGAGUCAGGGACAGCCUUCAGUGACAUUAAUCUGCAGGAGAAGGACUGGACUGACUAUGAUGAAAAGGCCCAGGAGUCUGUGGGAAUCUAUGAGGUCACCCACCAGUUUGUGAAGUGCUGAUCCCUCUUCCUUCCCAGUUGCCCUUAAGAACUGAGAAAGGACAAAGUACUCUAAGCAGCAGAGCCCACAGAGGCUCGUUCCUUUGACCCUUGUCUCCUGGUGGCUAUACGAAACCUUCACAAUCUGCAUGCUGGACUUUAUUACAGCUUCCCAAGCCCCAUCAAUAAAGCCCCUGUUCACGCUGCACUGGUGCAUGAAGGUGAAGUAAGGAGGCAGCUACUCCCUCCACAAAUAAGAAUUCGUGCAGCAGCAGUUCACUCCUUAGGAAAAUGAAGAGUAUUUUUAAGGAGAUGGUAUCUCCCCAGUCAAGGGCAAGUUUACAGAGAUGAAACCGCGAUCCCACCAUCACUCAAUGAGCCAGAAGCCAAUGGUGACGUACUGUUACCUGAACUUACUGAACUUGCUGUUGGAAAGAUCUUUGUGAGGAUUAGGAAUUAGGUUAAAAGAAAUUAAGAACCAUCUUCAAGCAAAAAUUAAACUUUAUUUCUGCUUAAACAAUAAAUACACCUGAGUUAGUUUUCCAAACCUUUCCUCCUGAUUAAAUGCCCUUAAAACUUAAA